CUUCUGCACUCACAGCCGAAGGGAAAGCAGCAGGUUGGGGCUUCUUGUGGCCAACUUCAGAGCCUGUCACCAGGAAAGGUAAGCAUGGGAGGAAGGAAGAUGGCGACAGAUGAAGAAAAUGUCUAUGGUUUAGAAGAGAACGCUCAGUCCCGGCAGGAGUCCACGCGGAGGCUCAUCCUUGUUGGGAGAACAGGGGCCGGGAAGAGCGCCACUGGGAACAGCAUCCUGGGCCAGAGACGGUUCUUCUCCAGGCUGGGGGCCACGUCUGUGACCAGGGCCUGCACCACGGGCAGCCGCAGGUGGGACAAGUGCCACGUGGAAGUCGUGGACACUCCGGACAUUUUCAGCUCCCAAGUGUCCAAGACAGAUCCUGGCUGUGAGGAGAGAGGUCACUGCUACCUGCUCUCGGCCCCCGGACCCCACGCGCUGCUCCUGGUGACCCAGUUGGGUCGGUUCACCGCCCAGGACCAGCAGGCGGUGAGGCAGCUGAGUCAUGGAGCUUUCAGCCCCAGCACAUGGCUCCUCCUUAACUGCGUCUGCUCAACCUCCCUCAGCCCUGUGAACAGCAUCCCCGCACACAGACGCAGAGCAGGACUCUCUCUGCUGCCACUUCACCUUCCUGAGAGAGGACCAGCGGCCAGAGCCUCAGUGACUGCCACCCUGGAGGACAGGGCACAACAACCGUUUCUGGAGAGAAUGGGAGGAUUCCAGAGGGGCAAAUAUGGAACUAUGGCUGAAGGUAGAUCAGAAGAUAACUUGUCUGCAACACCACCGGCAUUGAGGAUUAUCCUAGUGGGCAAAACAGGCUGCGGGAAAAGUGCCACAGGGAACAGCAUCCUUGGCCAGCCCGUGUUUGAGUCCAAGCUGAGGGCCCAGUCAGUGACCAGGACGUGCCAGGUGAAAACAGGAACAUGGAACGGGAGGAAAGUCCUGGUGGUUGACACGCCCUCCAUCUUUGAGUCACAGGCCGAUACCCAAGAGCUGUACAAGAACAUCGGGGACUGCUACCUGCUCUCUGCCCCGGGGCCCCACGUCCUGCUUCUGGUGAUCCAGCUGGGGCGUUUCACUGCUCAGGACACAGUGGCCAUCAGGAAGGUGAAAGAGGUCUUUGGGACAGGGGCCAUGAGACAUGUGGUCAUCCUCUUCACCCACAAAGAGGACUUAGGGGGCCAGGCCCUGGAUGACUAUGUAGCAAACACGGACAACUGCAGCCUGAAAGACCUGGUGCGGGAGUGUGAGAGAAGGUACUGUGCCUUCAACAACUGGGGCUCUGUGGAGGAGCAGAGGCAGCAGCAGGCAGAGCUCCUGGCUGUGAUUGAGAGGCUGGGGAGGGAGCGAGAGGGCUCCUUCCACAGCAAUGACCUCUUCUUGGAUGCCCAGCUGCUCCAAAGAACUGGAGCUGGGGCCUGCCAGGAAGACUACAGGCAGUACCAGGCCAAAGUGGAAUGGCAGGUGGAGAAGCACAAGCAAGAGCUGAGGGAGAACGAGAGUAACUGGGCAUACAAGGCGCUCCUCAGAGUCAAACACUUGAUGCUUUUGCAUUAUGAGAUUUUUGUUUUUCUAUUGUUGUGCAGCAUACUUUUUUUCAUUAUUUUUCUGUUCAUCUUUCAUUACAUUUAAAUCUCUGGACCCUGGAGCACUUCUAAUGUAUCACCCCAUGGAGUCAUUGUUCUAAUAAUCACCAAUUCAGACUCAGAUCCUCGUGGUCUAUGGAGCAUGCUGCUUGCUGUCUGUGCAGCUCCCAUUUCCCCUUCUUCCUGAUAGACUUGGAGCUGUGUGCCUCCACUCCAAGGCUGCCUGCCUGCUGUAAACACUAUUCCACUCUGUCUGCCAACAACUGCUUCAGGAAUGGGCCUGAGAUCCCAUGCAGGUCCCUGAGAAGUGAGUAAAAGUCCGCAGAGGUGGGGAUGGAAGAUCUCUCCUUAGAUAGAACCUGUCUUCCUCCCUGGCAUUGUGGGGUCUGGGCGUGACACUGGGACUCUCAGCAGCUUUGUGCUGCCAACCUGAGAUUGAAGGCAGUGCCUCAGAGCAGCACAGAGAGUUGGGGCCCCCUGAGCCCUGAGCCACCAGCCCUGCAGCCUGCCCUAUCUCCGCAUUUCCAGUUGUAUUAGCCAAUAGAUUUCCUACUUAUUUAAGCUAUUUGAGCUCCGGGUCUCUUCUACCUGCAUUCUAAAACAUUCAAAGUAAUAAAAAUUUCUCCACA